GCCCGGCCUUUGUCUCUCGUGCCCGCACGUGCGUGUCUCGGUCAGUAGCCCUGCGCUUCUCCUUCACUCUCGGCGGUUCAGGAGGCUCUGCCGCAGCCGGGGCCCUCCUGUGACCUGCAUGUACUGGGGGAUUCGCAGGGAGGAUGUCGGGACACCCCGGAAGCUGGGAAAUGAACUCGGUUGCCUUUGAGGAUGUGGCUGUGAACUUCACCCAGGAGGAGUGGGCUUUGUUGGAUCCUUCCCAGAAGAAUCUCUAUAGAGACGUGAUGCAGGAAACCUUCAGGAAUCUGGCUUCCAUAGGAAACAAAGGGGAAGACCAGAGCAUUGAAGAUCAGUACAAAAAUUCUUCAAGAAAUCUAAGGCACAUCAUAUCUCAUUCUGGAAACAACCCAUAUGGGUGUGAGGAAUGCGGAAAGAAGCCAUGUACAUGUAAACAAUGUCAGAAAACUUCCCUUUCUGUCACAAGGGUUCACAGAGACACAGUAAUGCACACUGGAAAUGGACAUUAUGGUUGUACAAUAUGUGAGAAAGUUUUUAAUAUUCCCAGUUCAUUUCAGAUACAUCAGAGAAAUCACACUGGAGAGAAACCCUAUGAAUGUAUGGAAUGUGGGAAAGCCUUAGGUUUUUCCCGUUCUCUUAAUAGACAUAAAAGGAUUCACACUGGAGAAAAACGCUAUGAAUGUAAGCAAUGUGGGAAAGCCUUCAGUCGUUCCAGUCACCUUCGUGACCAUGAAAGAACUCAUACUGGAGAGAAACCCUAUGAAUGUAAGCACUGUGGGAAAGCCUUCCGUUACUCCAAUUGCCUUCAUUACCAUGAAAGAACUCACACUGGAGAGAAACCUUAUGUGUGCAUGGAAUGUGGCAAAGCUUUCAGUUGUCUCAGUUCCUUGCAAGGACAUAUAAAGGCUCAUGCUGGUGAAGAACCCUAUCCAUGUAAGCAAUGUGGGAAAGCCUUCAGAUACGCCAGUUCCCUUCAGAAACACGAGAAAACUCAUAUUGCACAGAAACCCUAUGUAUGUAACAAUUGUGGUAAAGGCUUCAGAUGUUCCAGUUCCCUUCGUGACCAUGAAAGGACUCAUACUGGAGAGAAACCCUAUGAAUGUCAGAAAUGUGGCAAAGCCUUUAGUCGUGCUAGUACCCUUUGGAAGCAUAAAAAAACUCAUACUGGAGAAAAGCCCUAUAAAUGUAAAAAAAUGUAAAGGCUUUAAUCACUACAGUUUUUGUCAAAAACAUGAACAGUCACAUACUUGAGAGAAACUGUGAAUGUAAGGUGUAGGAAAGUACUUAAUUUUCCCAGAUUUCCUCAAAUACAUGAAACGAAUCAAACUGGAGAUAAACCCUAUGACUAUAAGCAAUAAGGUAAAGCAUUCAAUUUUUCCAUUUCUUUUUGAAAACUUGAAAGGACUCACUGAAGAAAAUCCAUAUGAAUGUUUAAAAUGUGGUAAGGCCUGCAGUUGUUCCAGUGGUAUUUGAUGGUAUAACAUAACUCAUUCUAGAGAAAAACUUUAUGAAGGUAUCGAAUGUGAGAAUGCCUUCAUUUAUCCUAUAACUCACUCAGAGACACAUGGUAACACAUACUCCAGAUUGACCUUAUAAAUAAAAGAAUGCCCACCAGAUUGAAAUCCUAGAAAUACAGAAAAUUCUGAAUUUUAACAAUUACUUUAAAGGUCAUGUGAAAACUCCCACUGGAAAUAAAUCCUGUAAAUGUAAAUAUUAUGGAAAACCUUAUGGAAAAUAAUUAUAGUACAAUUCUCAAGAAAAUUCACUAUGUGAAUGAGAUGUUUUAGGAGCUAUAAAUAAAUUGAAUAUAUUGGUUGCUCAUUUUUGAAGAGAGUCUCUAGAAUAUAGAUUUUCACUUCUUUUGAAAAAAAAAAAAUUGAGGUGAGACUUUUUUUUUUUUUUUUGAGAUGGAGUCUCACUUUGUCGCCCAGGCUGGUGUGCAGUGGCACAAUCUCAGUUCACUGUAAGCUCUGCCUCCCAGGUUCACGCCAUUCUCCUGCCUCAGCCUCCUGAGUAGCUGGGACUACAGGUGCCUGCCACCAUGCCCAGCUAAUUUUUUGUAUUUUUAGUAGAGAUGGGGUUUCACCGUGUUAGCCAGGAUGGUCUCAAUCUCCUGACCUCGUGAUCCGCCCGCUUCAGCCUCCCAAAGUGCUGGGAUUACAGGCGUGAGCCACCACGCCCAGCUGAGGCAAGACUUCUGUAAGUAUUCUUCAAGCAGUAGUACAAGAGUUAAAUAUGUAUUCUUCUUUUUUAAGCUGGUAAAUAAAUUUCCUUUUUCUACCCAUUUUAAAGUGUGUUGGUUAUAUGGGUAAAUUGAAAUGUAUUUCUUUUCCUUUUUUCUUGCAUAGCCAUUUUAAAAAAUAUUUUUUAAAUAUUUAAAGUAUAAAAUAUUUUUAAAAUUUUUUAAAAAUUUUGUGGGUUACACAGUAGAUGUGUGAAAUGUAUUUGUAGGUUUAACUUCUGUGUAGUUUAAUUAUUUUGUUAUUAAUUGGCCAUUGAUAAAUGAGUCUAUUUUCUUUGCUAAUAGAGUUGCUGUCAAUUUGUAAGUAUGUAAAGUUUAUUAUAGAGUAUAUUCUCACGUGAAUUAUUAUUUUCAUCUGUUGUUCUUUACAUUGUCAUUAUUUUUGGCUAUUUGCAUAGGUAACAUUGGUUUAAGGAGAGAGACCUGUGAUCGAACAGUGUCUUGUGUCUAAUCUGAGAAAGAAAGCAUCCAGUCUUAUCAUCAUGUAUGAUGUUAGCUGAGGGUUUUUAAAAUAAAUUCCUUAAAGCAGGUUGA